CUCCUUGCGCGGGUGAGAUUCGAGAGAUGGGGGACAGGCCAGGAGCUCAGACCGCUCUUUGAGACUCUCCCGAAGGAGAAUGGGAGGGUAGGGGCGCUGCCAGACUCCUUCCCUGGUGGGCCUAGAUGAAGACGCUCAAGGACCCUCGUGACUUGGCCGAGACAGGGGAAGGGAGAAGUUGAGUCGGGCAAGGAAGAGAUGCUAAAGCCUGGGGAAUUAAGAACAUGCCAGAAUCAUCCCGAGGGAGUCUGGAAUUAGGGAGGGUGAGGACUCGCUAGGAUCGUCCUGUGGAUCUGGCUACAGCAGGAGCUGAUGACCCUCAUGAUGUCUGGCGAUAAAGGGAUUUCUGCCUUCCCUGAAUCAGACAACCUUUUCAAAUGGGUAGGGACCAUCCAUGGAGCAGCUGGAACAGUAUAUGAAGACCUGAGGUAUAAGCUCUCGCUAGAGUUCCCCAGUGGCUACCCUUACAAUGCGCCCACAGUGAAGUUCCUCACGCCCUGCUAUCACCCCAACGUGGACACCCAGGGUAACAUAUGCCUGGACAUCCUGAAGGAAAAGUGGUCUGCCCUGUAUGAUGUCAGGACCAUUCUGCUCUCCAUCCAGAGCCUUCUAGGAGAACCCAACAUUGAUAGUCCCUUGAACACACAUGCUGCCGAGCUCUGGAAAAACCCCACAGCUUUUAAGAAGUACCUGCAAGAAACCUACUCAAAGCAGGUCACCAGCCAGGAGCCCUGACCCAGGCUGCCCAGCCUGUCCUUGUGUCGUCUUUUUAAUUUUUCCUUAGAUGGUCUGUCCUUUUUGUGAUUUCUGUAUAGGACUCUUUAUCUUGAGCUGUGGUAUUUUUGUUUUGUUUUUGUCUUUUAAAUUAAGCCUCGGUUGAGCCCUUGUAUAUUAAAUAAAUGCAUUUUUGUCCUUUUUUA